AACGGCUGCCUCGGCCCUCGGGCUGCUGAGGAGAUGGCGUCGGGCUCCAAGGCCUCGGUGCCCGCGGACUCAUUCCGCACCAUCAGCCCGGACAGGCGAGGCGAGAAGUCCGCCUCCGCUGUCUCCGGGGACACGGCGGCCGCGACCACCCUGAAGGGCACCGCGAUCCCAGUGCGGUCGGUGGUGGCCUCCCCUCGCCCGGUGAAGGGGAAAGCGGGCCGGGAGACGGCCAGGCUGCGGCUCCAGCGCCUGCCCGCGGCUCAGGCCGAGGACACGGGAGAGGCGGCGGCGGCGGCGGCGGAGGAGCCCCUGCUGCCAGUGCCUGAGGAUGAAGAGGAGGCGCAGCCCCUGCCCCCAGUCUGCGUGUCCCGUAUGAGGGGGAUGUGGCGGGACGAGAAGGUGUCGCUGUAUUGCGACGAAGUGCUGCAGGACUGUAAGUACAGAUGGGGUUUCUCCAGUUGGUCAGGCUGGACUCGAACUCCCGACCUCAGGCAGAAGAUGCUGAUGAAGUUAUGGGUAAAUACCUAUCAGAAAAAUUAAAGUUGAAAGACAAAUGGCUUGGAGUCUGGAAGACUAAUCCCAGUGUAUUCUUUGUGAAAUAUGAAGAAGCUUCUAUCCCUUUUGUUGGUAUAUUGGUUGAGGUAACUUGUGAACCAUACCAAGACUCAUCAUCUCGUUUCAAAGUUACUGUUUCUGUUGCUGAGCCCUUUUCUUCCAACAUUGCAAAUAUUCCAAGAGAUUUGGUUGAUGAGAUUUUGGAGGAACUGGAACACAGUGUGCCUCUUUUGGAAGUGUAUCCUGUUGAGGGACAAGAUACUGAUAUACAUGUUAUUGCUUUGGCCUUGGAAGUUGUCAGGUUUUUUUAUGACUUUCUUUGGAGAGACUGGGAUGAUGAAGAAAGUUGUGAGAAUUAUACUGCACUUAUUGAAGAAAGAAUUAAUUUGUGGUGUGAUAUACAGGAUGGAACAAUACCUGGUCCUAUCGCACAACGUUUUAAAAAAACUUUGGAGAAAUAUAAAAACAAACGUGUCGAGCUCAUUGAGUAUCAGAGCAAUAUUAAAGAAGAUCCAUCUGCAGCAGAGGCUGUUGAAUGCUGGAAAAAAUACUAUGAGAUAGUCAUGCUCUGUGGAUUACUGAAAAUGUGGGAAGAUUUACGCCUCCGAGUUCAUGGACCUUUCUUUCCAAGAAUUCUGAGGCGUAGGAAAGGAAAAAGAGAAUUUGGAAAGACUAUAACACAUAUUGUAGCAAAAAUGAUGACUACUGAAAUGAUAAAGGAUUUAUCUUCAGACACACUUCUCCAACAGCAUGGUGAUUUGGAUUUGGCUUUGGAUAAUUGUUAUAGUGGAGAUACAGUAAUAAUUUUUCCAGGAGAAUAUCAAGCUGCAAAUCUUGCUUUGUUGACAGAUGACAUCAUUAUAAAGGGAGUUGGAAAGAGAGAGGAAAUUAUGAUUACUUCUGAACCUUCUCGUGACAGUUUUGUGGUGUCCAAAGCUGACAAUGUGAAACUAAUGCAUCUAUCUUUGAUACAACAAGGGACGGUUGAUGGUAUCGUGGUGGUGGAGUCUGGUCACAUGACUCUAGAAAACUGCAUAUUAAAAUGUGAAGGAACAGGAGUGUGUGUUCUUACAGGGGCUGCUUUGACAAUUACAGACAGUGAAAUAACUGGCGCCCAGGGUGCUGGUGUUGAACUGUAUCCUGGAAGCAUAGCUAUUUUGGAAAGAAAUGAAAUUCAUCACUGUAAUAACCUCAGAACCAGUAACAGUUCAAAAAGCACCUUAGGUGGAGUUAAUAUGAAGGUUCUUCCAGCACCCAAAUUGAAGAUGACUAAUAAUCAUAUUUAUAGCAACAAAGGCUAUGGAGUAAGCAUUCUUCAACCAAUGGAACAGUUUUUUAUCGUAGCAGAAGAAGCUCUCAACAAAAGGGCUUCUUCAGGAGAUAAAAAAGAUGAUAAAAUGCUCUUCAAAGUAAUGCAAAAUCUGAAUCUGGAAAUGAAUAAUAAUAAGAUAGAAGCAAACGUCAAGGGGGAUAUCAGAAUAGUCACAAGUUAAAGCGUCUGAAUUGAUGUUAAAGUUUUAUAUUUCACAAAUUUGUUUAAUACAUGAUUCUCAUACCCCACUGAAAUGGUAGUUUCAAUUCAAAGCUUAAUUAAAAAAUAUUUAAAUAUCA